AGUCGAGGGCUGCAGGUGGUAGGCUGCGACCCCUUCCUCCCACAGCCCCUUCCCGCCCCUCGCCGGGCAUCCGCCGACAGGUACAUACCAAGAAAUUGAAUUGCUGAGUCACAGGAGAGAUUUACAAAUAGUGUUUUGGCAUCAUGGAACGUGUAGGUUGUACUUUAACGACAACUUACGCCCACCCUAGACCAACACCAACCAACUUUCUACCAGCCAUCAGUACCAUGGCCUCAAGCUACAGGGACCGCUUUCCCCACUCCAAUUUGACCCAUAGCCUGAGCCUUCCUUGGAGACCCAGCACAUACUACAAAGUCGCCUCCAAUUCCCCAAGCGUGGCCCCGUACUGCACCAGAUCACAGAGGGUGUCCGAGAAUACCAUGCUUCCCUUUGUUUCCAACAGAACCACUUUCUUCACAAGAUACACACCGGAUGACUGGUACAGGUCCAAUUUAACCAACUAUCAAGAGUCCAACACUUCCCGACAUAAUUCGGAGAAACUAAGAGUGGAUACAUCUCGCCUGAUUCAAGACAAAUAUCAACAAACAAGAAAAACUCAGGCAGACACAACCCAAAAUCUGGGAGAACGUGUCAAUGACAUAGGGUUUUGGAAAUCUGAAAUCAUUCAUGAGUUGGAUGAAAUGAUUGGAGAGACAAAUGCACUUACUGAUGUGAAGAAAAGACUGGAGCGGGCUUUGAUGGAGACUGAAGCCCCUCUUCAGGUAGCCCGAGAAUGUCUAUUUCAUCGAGAAAAGAGAAUGGGAAUCGACCUAGUUCACGAUGAAGUUGAAGCACAACUGCUGACGGAUGGCUUCUGUUGGGGAGGCAAUCAUGGUACUAUCUUCUUAGCACUCCCAGACCGUACUGACUCCUUGGACUUUGGAGCCAAAUGAACCUGCAAAGUCAUCUACCCUGCAGCCUGCCCUGGUCUGGCUCUGGGAUGGGGACUGAGACAGCUGCUCAGAACUCAGGCUGGGGCUCUGGGCCUGGCCCCAGCUGGCCAGUUUCCUUCCCACAAGAGGCUUUUCCUUCCUCCAUGCUGCAGAAGCAGAAAGCAAAAAUACUCCAGCCUCAGACGUUUGUUGAGAAUGCAACCAAUGAGUUCCAGAGAUGUCAGACCUGCUGCUGGAGAGACGUUUCAGCAUUUCAGCCCAGUCCAGUCCAAGGCGGUUCUCCUCUAAGGACAGGAUUGAAUAGAAAUCCUGCAACCAGCACGGAAAGAGGAUCUGGGUGGGCUCUCACCCCCAGCAAUAAGAACUAUACUCCUCACCUAGGUUUCUGCCUCUAAGCAGGUUGUGGGACCAGAAGCUUCUCACAAGCAGCCAUGCCAGAAAGGGUAGCUGAUGGGUCAUCUUGGCUGAACUCAGGAAUAAAUACUGAGAAUGCAGAUCUCUAAUGAAAGGAAAUGCCUCUGCUCACUAUACUCAAGGAUAAGUGAGAAGACAAGAAUAUUUGGUGAAUCUAUCAUUAAAAAGCAUUGUAUGUGGAAAUGAAAUAUCUGCACCUAUAGGUGGUAUUUGCUUAUUAGCUAGAUUCAAUUCAGGCUUGCAGCUUGACUUUGAAGAUUUGAUUUCAGUAGCCCAUUCACCUGUUAGACAGGAGGUUUACCCACUUUCCCAAGAUGUAAAAAGACUCAGUUAACACAGGUAAAUAGAACCACAUAUAAAGCCUCAACCUGUGGGAGCAGGGUCUGGGUUUAACAAGGACAUCCAAGUAAUGAUUUUAUAUCCACAACUCAGGCCACAGCGCGGGGUCAGCACUCAUCCACAUUUGUGGCUGCAACUCAAUGUUUCUGUGAUGUGGUGCAUAUUCCUCAGCUGACAGUAUAGCAGAGCCCACAUCUUACAUGAGGAUUCAGUUCUAAAGUCAUGAAAAUCACCCAUGUUACAAUAUUACGAGACCUAAUACUUAACUGAACACUCAGCAUCUACUAGGCACAUAAUUAUCUACCCAAUAGCCUGGAAAGAUGGGUAUUAUUACCAUUAGUUUAUUACUUGCCUCUGGUCAGGUUUAGCAAGUAGCAAAGACAUGUGAACCAGGGCUGUCUGACGCCGAAGCUUGUGGCUUUUGUUAACAUUUUAAUUUUGUAAAAAAUGUGUAUAUAUUCAUGGGGUACAAGUGCGAUUUCACUUCAUUGAUACAUUGCACUGUGGUGAAAUCAGGACCUUCAGAGCAUCUAUCACUGGAGCAACGCACAUUUAACCACCAAGCAACCUCCCAACAUCCCACCCUCCUCCCUCCCCUCCUUUGAGUCCCACUAUUCAUCAUUCCACACUCUCAAGGCAUAUGUUUUCAGCCACUGUUCCAGCCAAGACCUGGGAGUGUGCACAAGAAGGGAUUUUCACUUGAGGUGAUGGGAAGUAAAAGGCUGUGAAGUCUCUAUUCCACCUCCCCAAGCCCCACCUCCCAAGAGGUGAACUGUAACGACAGAUGCUUCAUGAACAUUUCAGCCGCUCAAAUAGUAGGAUGCAUUCAAGGUUCUUCAAGCAACUGGACAUGAUUCCAUGUUUUGUUUUCAUCCAAAGCCCCACAGAUGAAACUGCAUUUUAAUCACUUUAGUCACUGCAAUCUGAGAAGCUCAAUGAAGUCAGUGUGACCCUGUAACUCAUGGGGCCUGUAAUUUCUCCCUAAGUCAGGGAUCUGGAAAUGUUGGACCCAUUUUCCAGGCUCCUAAAUGUACGGUUCACUUCCUUAGGUGUGAGGCAGCAGCCAGAGAUCUAGUUAGAUGAAGGCUCUUCCUACGCUUCUGCUUUCUGUGUGUAUCCCCCACCUUUUUGCAACUUUCUUCUCUUGGGCAGGUGAGGGAAUGCUUUGUCCUUCUUUUGCUGUAUUGUGGUAUUUCAAGGCCACCUCCAUGUAUGGGUACAGAUGGAAGGAUAAGUUAGCACUGGGGACAGUGCCAGAGGCCUUUGGCUUUGGGCUUUUUGUAUUCUUGUGAACCCUUCUGCCUCCAACCAUCUGGCAUUCAUCAUAUGACAUUAUU